CAUACAGGUUGCAGUCUGGGGUAUCCGGUCCUUCACAGACAAUUUCUCAGAUGCGGGGCAGAGCAGGAUGAUCAUCUUAUUGGCAUUUAUGGUUGACCCCUGCGGAAGCAUUACAUUGGAGGAAACACAAUAACUGAAAAACCAAGUCUCUUAUGCUAUAUUAUGGAGUUAAAGAAUGGAUUUUCUGUUUCCCCAAGAAAUAGACACCAUGCUGUGAAAGAAGUUAUGGUUUCUCACUGGAAGCAAGAAAACUCAUGCAAGAAAUGUGUCUGUAGGGAAUGGCCACCAAUAUGCUUCAUACCAACAAUACACAGUUUCACCCUUCCACCUUCCUCGUAGUGGGGGUCCCAGGGCUGGAAGAUGUGCAUGUAUGGAUUGGCUUCCCCUUCUUUGCAGUGUAUCUAACAGCCCUUCUAGGGAACAUCAUUAUCCUGUUUGUGAUACAGACUGAACAGAGCCUCCACCAACCCAUGUUUUACUUCCUAGCCAUGUUGGCCGGCACUGAUCUGGGCUUGUCUACAGCAACCAUCCCCAAGAUGCUGGGAAUUUUCUGGUUUAAUCUUGGAGAGAUUGCAUUUGGUGCCUGCAUCACACAGAUGUAUACCAUUCAUAUAUGCACUGGCCUGGAGUCUGUGGUACUGACAGUCACGGGCAUAGAUCGCUAUAUUGCCAUCUGCAACCCCCUGAGAUAUAGCAUGAUCCUUACCAACAAGGUAAUAGCCAUUCUGGGCAUAGUCAUCAUUGUCAGGACUUUGGUAUUUGUGACUCCAUUCACAUUUCUCAUCCUGAGAUUGCCUUUCUGUGGUGUCCGGAUUAUCCCUCAUACCUAUUGUGAACACAUGGGCUUGGCAAAGUUAGCUUGUGCCAGUAUUAAUGUUAUAUAUGGAUUGAUUGCCUUCUCAGUGGGAUACAUUGACAUUUCUGUGAUUGGAUUUUCCUAUGUCCAGAUCCUCCGAGCUGUCUUCCAUCUCCCAGCCUGGGAUGCCCGGCCUAAGGCACUCAGCACAUGUGGCUCUCACGUCUGUGUUAUGUUGGCUUUCUACCUGCCAGCCCUCUUUUCCUUCAUGACACACCGCUUUGGCCACAACAUCCCUCAUUACAUCCACAUUCUUCUGGCCAAUCUGUAUGUGGUUUUUCCCCCUGCUCUUAACUCUGUUAUCUAUGGGGUCAAAACAAAACAGAUACGAGAGCAGGUACUUAGGAUACUCAACCCUAAAAGCUUUUGGCAUUUUGACCCCAAGAGGAUCUUCCACAACAAUUCAGUUAGACAAUAAUGAGAUCAUAACAAAAUAAACACUGGAAACAUUUUUUUUACUACUUCUCUUGCAUUCCCACAUGAGCCAAUAGCAUUAUAUCCCCUACAACGUCUCAUGAUUUCAGUACGGUCUGUUGGAAGUUAUAGCUCAAAGAUUCCAAAACAAUCUCUCUGUUUCACCCAUUAAAAGUGCAAAAAGUACUCACACUUAAGCCCCAUGAUACUACAAAAUGCCUAAAGAGAAACAAAGGCUUUGUAAAAGUUAUUGCCCAGUAAUUGUCUUGAAUAGCCUUUCCACAUGAAGAUUCUCUGUAUUUACAUAUCCAAAGCUGAAGUUCAUGACGAUUAAAAUGAUGUGGUAUUUCAUCAAAACCAGGCAGGAUACAGUGGCAAGAGAAAUUAACUAGGAGUCAUAAGAUCUAGAUUUAAAUACAGGUUAUGGCCUUACCUAAAAUUUUGACCUGAGCAUUUCACUUAGACUCUUUGAGUUCACAAUAACAAAUUCAUACUGAUUUAUAGCAUUUUAUGAGCAGGGAUAUUGAAGCUUAAAGUGAAUGUUGUGAAAAUCUGUGCAGCUUGUAAAACAUUAAAAGAUUUGGAAACAAAAUGAGUGCUUACUAAACAUAAUUAUAGUGUAAUUGUUAUUUCUAAUGUAUGUAGAUUUCAUUUACUAAUCCACUCUAGUAUACAAUCCCUGGUUUGAGGUCAGCUCUCCAGAUCCAGAUUAUCCCAACGCAUGGGCCUCUUCAUGGACCUCUCAGCUCUUACCUUCGUGAAAGAGACUUUCAGUCAGGAGACUAUAAAGCUUGAAGAGUUAACAGGUUUCUGUCUUGGGCUUAAGGACUCAGGGAAAUCCCAUCCUCCACAGUCUUUGCUAGAGUGGGUUUUAGGGCAGACUGUAAUAGUGUGGCUGCUGAAAUAAUAUAAAGUCAUUCUUAAUAAGGUAUAGAAGAUAAAUAGGACAAUUUAUUUCUUUGGGUAUUCUAGGA